GAGAAGGAAUUCGGAGCAGACGCGAGGCCCGGCGCUCGCGCCGCGCCCGGGAGCCCGGGAGGGAGACCGGCAGCGGCGGCAUGAGGCAGGCGACGCGGCGCUGGUGAGCAGCGCGCGCGGCGGCGGCGGCGGCGGCGGCGGGGACCUUGGCGCGGCCGGACGCGGGCGAGCGCCGAACGGCCGGGGGCUCCCCUCCCCCGCUGCCGGGCCGUGAUUUGCCGGGCCUGCUGCGCCCCCCGCCCACCCCUUGCCUCAGCCGCCGCCUCGCCGCUUCCCCUCGUCGGAGCGGCCGCUCGUCCGCCCGGCUUGAGGCCCGCGGGGAGCGCGGCGCAAUUCGUCGGCCCGCGGGGGGGCGGCCUCCCGGCAUCUUCGCGGCGACCAAGGACUACCAGGAAGGGGAGCGGCUGGGAUGGCGCGUCCGCGGCCCCGCGAGUACAAAGCGGGCGACCUGGUCUUCGCCAAGAUGAAGGGCUACCCGCACUGGCCGGCCCGGAUUGAUGAACUCCCAGAGGGCGCUGUGAAGCCUCCAGCAAACAAGUAUCCUAUCUUCUUUUUUGGCACCCAUGAAACUGCAUUUCUAGGUCCCAAAGACCUUUUUCCAUAUAAGGAGUACAAAGACAAGUUUGGAAAGUCAAACAAACGGAAAGGAUUUAACGAAGGAUUGUGGGAAAUAGAAAAUAACCCAGGAGUAAAGUUUACUGGCUACCAGGCAAUUCAGCAACAGAGCUCUUCAGAAACUGAGGGAGAAGGUGGAAAUACUGCAGAUGCAAGCAGUGAGGAAGAAGGUGAUAGAGUAGAAGAAGAUGGAAAAGGCAAAAGAAAGAAUGAAAAAGCAGGCUCAAAACGGAAAAAGUCAUAUACUUCAAAGAAAUCCUCUAAACAGUCCCGGAAAUCUCCAGGAGAUGAAGAUGACAAAGACUGCAAAGAAGAGGAAAACAAAAGCAGCUCUGAGGGUGGAGAUGCGGGCAACGACACAAGAAACACAACUUCAGACUUGCAGAAAACCAGUGAAGGGACCUAACUACCAUAAUGAAUGCUGCAUAUUAAGAGAAACCACAAGAAGGUUAUAUGUUUGGUUGUCUAAUAUUCUUGGAUUUGAUAUGAACCAACACAUAGUCCUUGUUGUCAUUGACAGAACCCCAGUUUGUAUGUACAUUAUUCAUAUUCCUCUCUGUUGUGUUUCGGGGGGAAAAGACAUUUUAGCCUUUUUUAAAAGUUACUGAUUUAAUUUCAUGUUAUUUGGUUGCAUGAAGUUGCCCUUAACCACUAAGGAUUAUCAAGAUUUUUGCGCAGACUUAUACAUGUCUAGGAUCCUUUUAUCAAGGCAGUUAUGAUCAUCGUUUUCCUGCCUUGACCCCACCAUCAUCAAACACUCAGUUAAAUAUAAAUUAACAUUUUUUAGAUGACCACUCAACAUAAUGCUUAAGAAUGGAAUUUCCUCUCUGUGACAGAACCCAGGAAUUAAUUCCUAAAUACAUAACGUUGGUAUAUUGAAGACGAAAUUAAAAUUGUCCUUCAGUUUUGAGGCCAUGUGUAAAGUUUAACCAUAUUGUAAAAUAUCUAUUCCGUAUUAGAAAUAGCUAGUUGACAGCUUAUACUUCUCAAAAUUCAUAUUGUUAUGUACACAAACUAAGUUUCUAUAUGUGAAGUUAGUGAGUCUUUUUGUGUUACUCCAAAAUAAAGGCAAUGAUUUAUUUUUUUCCCAGUGCCAAUACAAUUUUGAGCUAAGCACUCAAGGUGGAUACUUUACAUUUUAAAGCUGGAAUCAGCAACAGCCCUAUGGGAAACCAGACAAAGCAUUGACUUUUAAAUGUAGACUUUUAAAAUAAACUGUUUUCUUUUGGAACUACAAUUAGAAUAGUUAAUAUUCAUCCUUAAACCAUUAUUAUGUGUACAUUAUUGUUGCUAUUGUGAUAAUAGAGAAUUUUAUUUAUUUUUAUGCCAGCUUAUAUUGUGAGAACACAUUUAGUCAGUUUGGGUUUUAUCAAUCCUGUUAAUGCUUGUCCUUGGAACAUCUUUCGCGUAUUCACGGUUUGUAGUUGAAAAGUUUACUGUAAAAAAAUCAAAAACAAAAAAAUGUAUUGUUUUUACAGAAUAAAUUUAUUGGAAUGUGUACUGGGAGUAAGAUUUGAGGUUGUAAGCAAACUAAGUUAGUGUAAUUUGGCUUCAUAUAUGUAACGUGAGGUAUUAAUGUAAUUCAUAUAUUAAAGCAAAAAUUGUUCACAGCAAGCUGACAAUAGAAUCAAGUGCAGGUGAGGGUUUUUCUUUUUCUUUCUUUUUUUUUUUUUAAACACUCUCUGGGUUUUAGAUUAUUUGAAAACACUGUAGGGGAUGAUGGGGAGAUGACUACAUGAUUUGCUUACACUUACAUAUUUACCAGCCCAGUGGACCCUAGAUUUUGUAAUUUGAUAUUAUCCAUGCAUUGAUUUGUAUCCCAUUUUCUUUUGGUUUUCUUGAUGAGAGCUAAUAAAAACAUGAGAAAAUGUGAGCAGACCUAAAAGCCUAGGGCCGUUAAUAAUGAUGAUGGUGAUGAUGGCAGCUAAGGGUAUGAAAGCACCAGUCCAUUUAUCAUUCCAGGGCACAGUGAGGAGGUGGCUGUUUGUAUUUUUGGUGUGUUUCUUUCAUUUAGUGAAUACUGAUUUUCUCUAGUAUACUCAACAUACAAUCCCAAACAUGAAAAGUUCAUAAAAAGAUAGUAGGGAUGUCGAUCUAAUACUUCUUCCUUAAAAGGUCCUUUUUAAUUUUGAAUAUUUGAAUGUAUUUUUUAAUUAAUGAAAUUUAAUUCAUCAAAAGACCUCUUCAUUGCUCACACUGAAACAUAAGGGGAAUGUAGAUGGCAUUUUGAAUUGGAAUAUACAACUCACAAAUUUUCUUUAAAAGCGUUUUAUGUGUAUAUAUGAAAUGUUUCAAAUUUAAUAAGAUUUGUCUUUAUAAGAGGCCAAAAAUAAUUUUAUUAAAAAUAUACACAGAAAUACAAUAGAAAUAUUUCCAGCCACCAAUAAAACAAAUGUUCAUUAAGGAUAGAGAUAAAGUUACUGAUCCCUAUUUAGCUGUUUAAAUUCACACAAAAAAAUUUAGUAAAAGUAAUUUUCUUGAAACAGCAGCAAAUAAUAAACUUUCCUUGGGAAAACAUUUUUCAAACAACAUUUAAAAAUAUUCUGAUGAUUUGCCUUUUAUAUUGAGUUUAAUAAUGAAGCAUAUUCAUCUUAUUUGCAAAAGUUACUCCUCCAGUCUGCAUUCACUGUUUUGAAUUUUUUAAUAUGCACAGGCCAUAUUCUCUUUUGAAUAGUUUCAUUUCAUGCUCACUACUGUUGGCACUAAAUUGUAAUUUUUUACACUUAUAAUUAUUUUAUAUGUCAAACAAUAUUGAGAUGGAUGAUCAAGUUUAUUCACAAAUGAUUUUGAAUAUAUUUCUUUAAACAAACUGUUUCUCAAGAAUUUCCAUUUUCCUUCAAAAAAAAUUUACACAAUACCAUAUAGCUCACACAUACAGUGCAGAGCAAGAAUGUACAUAUUCUUAAGUACUCACGUAUGAGAAGAGAGUGAAAUGGGACAAAAUAUCAGUACCAGUAUAACAAAAGUUAGUAAUUUAGAAAGGAGGAACAUGAAGUAAUAUUUUUAUUCCACUUUUUCUUCUGCCUUUGUUUUUAUGAAGAACUCUGGUUUGUAGAUACAACGAUAGGCCAAGAGCUGAGGAAGAACUCCAUAUGCUAUGUUUAAUGCUAAAAAAAGGAUUUUUGCUUCUUCAGGGACUCUGUAGACAUAAGCAGUUCUAGCAUGAAGAGAUGCACCAAUGUGAGAAAACUGAGCCUGUUGCAUUUAAAAAAAAAAAAUUGAGUAAGCAUGAAACGUGUUCAGUUGGAUGCAUGAUGAGUUCUGAAUGGUUCAUUCAGGCUACGUUUCUGUGCCCUCAAAACCAGUCUCACCUGCAGGCAAAAUACCUUCAAACAAUCCAGAGUCUUUAAUGUCAGAGUCUUUCAUUAAAUUUAGUCCUUGAUUAAAUUUAGGGCCAUUCUUGAUAUGACUGUUCAAAUAAAGUAGAUAUUAUUUAGUGUAGUUUUAUCAUGCCAGUUGUGUUUUUUAACCAUCAAGUGCCCCUUACCGAACAUUAGUGGCUCAAUCUAAUAGAAAAAUCUGAAUAAAAUCUCAAAUUUUUUUCUGAUUUGCGUUCUGGAGAUCCUGCAUACAGACUCAGUUGUGGUUCACAAAUUGCGUUCCAAUAAAAAUGAAGAAAGCGCAGAGUUUUAAAAAACAAAUAUUUUUAGCAUAAACUAUUGAAAGGGAAGCACUGGGGGGACCUCAGCUUCAUUUAUCAGUCUUUCAUCUACUCCUUGCAGCAAGAGCUCAUACCCUUUCCCUAUGUGUUUUUUGUUUAUUCAUUUAUUCAUGUAUUUGUUUUUUCUGCAGCUUUUAAAAUAUUAAGGGUUGUUUGUAAGAUAAGGUUGUUACCAACUUGGGUGGAGGUAGGAGUACGGUUGCUCUUUGUAAAAUGGCAAAUGUACAUGCAGGCAACCUUUUUAAAUCAAAUUAUAAUUUAUUUAGAAGUACGACAUGUCAGCAUUAUCCGCAUUUGCAAAAUGGCCUCCCUCUCUACUUAUAUACUUAUUCAGAAAACACAUUCAGAAUGUGCCAAUUGGUCUUUUUUGAUAUUUUUCGCAAGCACAGAGGAAAACCGUAUUGGAAAGGGUAAAACAGACCACAGCAGGAUUAAAAGCUCCUGUCAGAAAAUUUCCUCAGAAGGCUUGUAUCAUUACAAAAUGUACCCCUGGAGUCUGCAUUUUCAUAUCUUGCUGAAAUUCAAGAUACACAUGAAUAAAGGAUUGGGAAUCUAAAUGUAAUAAGUAGUAAAUUAUCAGUUCAUCAGGAUCAAAGAGACAAAAGACUGCACUAUAGAGAAGGCAUAGAAGUAACAAGAAUGAAGAACUAGAUAAUUUGCUUUAAAUACAUAUAAGUUAUUUUACAUUUCUUCCAUAUGAAACCAAUUUAUUCUGCUGAGUGAUUUCACAGAUAAAGGUGUUACUUACUUGACUUCACCAUGACAAGAAAAGGACAAGUUUUUUUAAGCAGCAUCUUUAUGAAUUUUUUAUCAGUGGCAGAUAUUUUAAUGGGCUGCAUUUUUACAAAUUCCUGAUAUAUUCUGGAGACCUGUGGUACAUUUUUGCUACUCUGGAGAUAUAAAUUAAAUUAGCAUGAUGUAUUGCCAAGGACCAGCACGUGGAUUGUCUACAUUGUGAUCCAUGAGGCACUGAGAGGACUCGGCCCUCAGAUACAACUCCCCUGGGUAGAUGCCCAGGCAGAACCCAGCAAAUGUAUAUGCAUCUCUGGGCUCUGAGGACAAAAUGCCUUGAGAGUAAAGGGCACUUUCAGGGCUGCCCUGAGGAGGUGCUUUCUGGACAUUCUAGGAACUCUGAGCAGGAGCAUGGCUCCCAUACUGUUUUUCCUUAGGGCCUGUUUUGAAUAAUAGUGUUUUUCUGAAUAUAUAACCAAGCAUUUUCUCUGGACUGGAAGCCACAUUUGAUCCCUGGUUCUCAGAAAUCUGGGUUUGGUGGUUCUGUCUUUAUAGAUACUUGUACACAUCACAAAAUCACCAAAUUUGGGGAAAUGCCAACCAUACUUUGAGAGAAUAAAUAUGAGCAGUUGUGCCUACUUGCAUAGGGGAGCCUGUGUAAAAAGUCAGUGAUUCCGUAGGCUCUUUUCCUGCACUAACCAGUGCAGUUAAUACCUCACUUUCAUGAACAGCAAACUCAUGGCAACAUUAAGUGAAUCAUGGCCGGGCGCAGUGGCUCACGCCUGUAAUCCCAGUACUUUGGGAGGCCAAGGCGGGUGGAUCACCUGAGGUCAGGAGUUCAAGACGAGCCUGGCCAACAUAGUGAAACCCCAUCUCUACUAAAAAAUACAAAAAAUUAGCCGGGCGUGGUGGCAGACGCCUGUAAUCUCAGCUGCUCGGGAGGCUGAGGCAGGAGAAUUGCUUGAACCCGGGGAGUGGAGGUUGCAGUGAGCCAAGAUUGUGCCACUGCACUCCAGCCUGGGUGACAGAGUGAGACUCUGUCUUUAAAAAAAAAAAAAGAUUCAUGUCCUUAGAUUAGAUUGUAAGCCCACUGGGCAGGUACUGUGUCUAAUGUUUUGUGUGGCACCUGUCACAUUGUUAGAGCUCAAUAAACGUUCAACAACAAUGGACUUGUGACUGUCAAAAUACAAAAAGGGUCUACAAAGCAUUUCUCUAGUUUUGUAUGUAUUUUAGUAGGCCUCUUUAUUCAGAAUUAUUAAACAAGGCACAAAAAUUUUAACAUUCAUAAUCAAAAGAGGCAUUUGUAUGUGAGAGAAGAACUCUAAGGCCAGUGGUGUGCAGCUCCCAGUACUGCUCAUAGUCCUAAUGGAUGUACUUAUGGUGGCCACACUUCCAGCUGAGUGAGCACCUGACCAUAGCUUUCUCCUAAGGCAUAGGAUGUUAAGUGUUCAGGGUUCUGAAGUUCAGAAAAACAGUCUCACCUGAGGAGGUUUCUCUUCCCAAGCACAUAGCUAAUAAAGGGCUGCAGGUUUUCUCCUGGGUGAUGUUCCCAGCAGCACAAGGCCUCUCAUGGCAGGACCUGAAGAGCUCAGCCUGAGCCUGUGCUGGGGUCAGGUGGCUCAGUGAACUCAAUGCUGCUGAAUUAACAGGAGGCCCAGGAUUACAGAUAUGAGUUGUUGAUCCUAGAAAUUUCUCCAGAAUUUAGCAAUGUGAGGUUGAGUCCCUAAUAAUUUUUCUUCCACUUCAUUCUAAAUCAUUUUCACCUUACAGAAAUAAUUAAGAGAUAUACUCUGAUUUUUUUUUAAGAAUGGAUGAUUGGAAUGGCAAAUGAGACAAUAAGGUGAACAAAGGUUAAAUUUUAAGAGCUGUUUUCUUACAUGUAUAGAGACAAUCUGUAAAGGAUAACUAAAAAAGUUAAUCGUGGUUCCACAAGGAGGAACUGAAAGAGUGUUAUAUGUCCAUGUGAAUGUUAUAGGCAGAAAACUUAGGUGACCAUUGGGAUGAUAGCCAGGGUCUUUUGCUAAUACAGUAUAAAUAGCUAAUCUAGAACUGUGUUAUCUUUUCUUAGAGUUUUCUGAGCAACAUAGUUCAUUGGUUCAGAACACUGACUUUGGAACUAGACAUCCAGAGUCAAAUCACAGCUCCACCACAAACCAGCCGUAUGGCCUCGGGUGAGGUGUGGAACCCACCUCAUAGGUUGUUAUGAGGGUUCAGUGAGGUGAUGUUUGUGACAUGCUUAGACAGUGUCAAGCACUUGGGGCUAUUCUGUAGACACAAGUACAAAACUGAAAUACCCAUUCAUGAUCUGGUGCUCGACUGUAGAAAAUCUGGGCCCUUUGUUUUUAGAUUCUCUUGACCUUUUGACCUUUUUACUGUGAGUGUCUCCAUGAAAGGAUAAGUACAUAAAAGAUGUUAAAUCAGUAUAAUUUAAUACUAAAUAAAGAUGUUUAGCAAUGAAUCACACCAGAAGCAAAUGAAGAAAACAAGAUUUGCAUUAGUAUCCCAACUAUCCGUGUUCUUCCUAAACUGUUACUUUCAGAUUUUUCUUAACGUCUCCAUGAGGGAAAAACCGUAUGAAAUUUACUUCCAGGCUGAGCGUGGUGGCUCAUACCUAUAAUCCCAGCACUUUGGGAUGCCAAGGCGGGAGGGUCACUUGAGUCCAGGAGUUUGAGACCAGCCUGGGCAACAUAGCAAGACCCUGUCUCAAGUUAAAAAAAAAAUGAUAAAUUUACUUCAGUAAACUCUUCACAACCAAAUUAUUCACACGUAAGUUUCCAUAUCUCUUUGUGAGAAAAAGACAUGACAUAGCACCUACAUAGCCAGGGAGUUAGAGAGUCUGAGGGCAGCACCUGACUGAAGUAACUGAACCUCCUUCGCUGGCUGUGGGAUGGCAGGCUCCUUACCAAGCCCAUGGUGAGUCUGUCCCAAAGCUUUCACCCAGUUUCUUUGUUUUCUUGGUAAUUAUAUACAAUACACUUAAUUUAAUUAGUUUGUCUUCAGGUUAAUCUUCGGAACAACAUAAGGCAUAUCUCCAAAUUCUUACUGGGAAUCUUCUACCAGUAAUAGUAGCAACAAAGGGUUACAUAGCUGUUAUGUGCCAGACACUGUUUUAAGCCCUUUACAUGUAUUACCUCAUCCAACCCUAACAGCAAUUCCAUGAGAAAGCUACUGUUAUUAUCCUCACUUUACAGAAGAGGAAACUGAGGAUCAGAGAGGUAAAGUAGCCAAGGUCAUUGUGCUCAUCAGCAACAGGCUAGAAUCUGAACCAGUUCACCUCCAGAGCUUAUGUUCCUAACUAUAUGAACUCUACUGGCUUUGGCUUUUUUUCAUUUUCAUUGAUAUUUUAGCAGAGAAAAUGCUUCAAUUGAUAGGAAAUGCUAAUAAGUGGAUCUAAGCAGCCUAUAAUGCCUUUCAGAUUACACUUGCAGCUUUAAUCCUAUGGUUAGCAUUUUAUAUGAAAAGAUACCUGGGUUAUGAGUAAGUCCCCAGUGGAACUCUUUGGUCUAAAAUGUGUCCUGGUUUCAUUUUAUUCAAUCUUCUUUUACUCUUUCCUUGAUCUUUUGAUUUCUGAAGGCAGCAGAUUUGGCAGACUCCUACAUGGUCUGAAAUCAAGGCCCCAAUAACUACUCACUCUUUUUUCUUUCUUUUUUUUGAGACAGUCUUGCUCUGUCACCCAGGCUGCAGUGUAGUGGGCGUGAUCUUGGCACACUGCAGCCUCUGCCUCCCAGGUUCAAGCGAUUCUCCUGCCUCAGCCUCCCAAGUAGCUGGGAUUAUAGAUGCCCACCACCACACCCAGCUAAUUUUUUGUAUUUUUAGUAGAGACGGGGUUUCGUCAUGUUGGCCAGGCUGGUCUCAAACUCCUGACCUCAGGUGAUCCACCUGCCUGGUCCUCCCAAAGUGCUAGGGUUACAUGUGUGAGCCACUGCGCCUGGCCACUACUCAAUAUUUCUUCCAUUGGCCUAUACUGAUCUAGAACUUUUCAAAGGUGGUUUUUUUUUCCCUUACUAAGUUGCAUAGAUUCUUGAGAGUUUACUAGAUGUUUCAGUAAAAGUAAGUUUUAGUAAAGUUAGUGGGAUCAUGAAUGCAUAAGGUUUCUAAAUAAGAAUGGCAAUUUUAGCAAGCAAAGAUGCUGAUUAAAGUUACAGAAAAAUGCCUAUUUUUGUUUUGUUUUGUUUUUUUGUGGUGGUGGGAGAGACAGGGUCUCUCUCUGUCACCUGGGCUGGAGAGUGCAGUGACACAGUCUCGGCUCACUGCAACCUCUGCCUCCUGGUUCAAGUGAUCCUCCCACCUCAGCCUUCCUAGUAGCUGGGACUGCAGGCAUAUGCCAUCACGCCAGCCUAAUUUUUGUAUUUUUUGUAGAGAUGGGGUUUUACCAUGUUGCCCAGGCUGGUUUCAAACUCCUGACUUCAAGCAGUCCACCCACCUCGGGCUCCCAAAGUGCUGGGAUUACAGGUGUGAGCCACCGUGCCUUGCUGGAGAGUGCUUUCUGUGAUGAAUGUGUCAGAUACUCCCAUAAGAUGAGACUCCAUUUCAUAAGCGAGUAUUUGCUAAGUACAAAACAAAUAACGUAAUUCAGUAUUCUGGUCAUAUCUAUUGUUUUGUUGCGGCAUGGCUUCUAACUUUUCCUUAGCCUACACACUAUAAGUGGGUAGAUAUUAAAGCUCAGCCAAGAGCUGUGGGAAUCAGACCCAUAAUUCUUUACUCAGUCUGUCUUCACCUGCUGGGCUGGGAGAAACAUCCUUCUGACAUUUACAGGAUCUGGUCCUUAGCCUUAGGCUCUGGAUCUGGGCAUUCACCAUCAAGAGAGGGGCUUCAGGCUGCCUUAUCAACUGGGCAGUGAUGGAUAAGCCCCAGGAUGCCUGACGUCUGACAUGAAUGAGGUAAUGCCCCUGCGGCUGCCAGCUGCUCUGUAGUCCACACUGCCCUUCUCAGAACCACUUGGCUGGAGUAAUAAGUGCCCACCUGCAAGCUUAGCUUCACCAACAGAUUAGGGUUUGUCUUAUUGCUACAGGCUUACCACACCCAUUUUCCUCUAAGCUAUGACCUUCCUAAGCUUCCUGACUGUUGACCCUGGCCAUGUGACUAGGCUUUUGCCUAGGUUUUCCUGCUGUUUCCAUUUGUCUCCUGAGACUUGACCAGGUCCAACAUCUGGUCUCUUUAACCAGCCUGCUGGCUGAUGACACUUAGCAUUCCUGCAUCAGGGACUGGUACCAGGCCGACCAGGCACAUGGCAGGCAGAGGAGGCCUGAUUGUGCAGGCAAAGCACAAUUGACACAGGUAAUAGGUGUCAAACUGAACAGCUGUCAAACUGAACAGUCUAAUCCUCUAAAGAAAGGGCUGGCAAGAGUGAAGUGGGUAUGCGGCCAUCUGUUCUGAAGGAUACAGGAGAAUAAGGCAGAGGAACCAGGCCAAAAAAAAAGGCAAGGCUUACUCUGCCCUCAGACCUGCUGCAUAUGCCCACACCUCAGUGUUUCCCUGGGUUAUUCCCUGGAGAGGCUCAGCCUAAUAAAGCCCCACUUGGCCCUCAGAGUCCAACUCGGAAUGUCACUGCCUUCCACCCACAAGGUUCUCCAGCACCUCGUACUACAUACAGUCUUUUGUGCUGUAGGACUCUGUGCCAUAGUUCAUUGUUUGCAUGGGGUGGGUGAGAUAACACAAUGGAGAAGAAUAUGAGCUUUGGAGUCAGACAGGAUUUCAUAAACCUAUUCUGCCAUUUAAUAACUGUAAUCUUAGGCAAAUAAUUUCAGGUGGACUGAGCCUCAGCCUCCUCAUCUUUAAAUUGGGGUUUUUUUCCCAGAGCUAUUACAAAAGAUAUUAUUAUGUGUCCAUUGUGCUGUUUAUUCUGAGGCAGGCAGGAAGACCACAGUCACCAGCCUCCCCUCAGUUGACCUGGUGCCAGGCCUGGACCUUGAAAAUAUCCCACAUGAUCUUUGCAUAAAAAAGAAUUAAAAUUUUAAUUGUGUUAAGCUACUCUGAGUAUUUGUUACAGCAGCAGAGCACAUAGCCUAUCCUUAGACAAAUAGGUAAGUAAAACUUUUAACGUGGUUUGCCUGGCAUGAAGUAAGGUAAUGAGAGCUCAGACUAGUGUAGGGGCAGCGGAGCUGGAAAAAAAAAAUGGGUUGGAGAAUCACUGGAGUAAAACUAACUGGACCUGGUUGGGUGUGGUGGCUCACACCUGUAAUCCUACCACUUUGGGAGGCUGAGGCAGGAGGAUUACUUGAAGCAGGCAUUUGAGAAUAAGCUGGGCAACAAAAUAAGAUCCCAUCUCUUUAAAAAAUUUAAAAAUUAGCUGUGUGCGGUGGUGUAUGUCUGUAGUCCCAGCUACUCUGGAGACAGAGGCAGGAGGAUUGCUUGAGCCUAGGAGUCCGAGGCUGCGGUGAGCUAUGACUGUGCCAUCACACUCCAGCCUGGGAGAUGGAGCAAGACCCUGUCUCUUUAAAAGAAAAAAAAAAGGACUUAGUGGUGGUCUAGAUGUAGAGGAUGAGGAGUGUAAAUAAUUACUCCAAGUUUCUGGCUUGAGUUGCUGGAUGCAAUUGGACUAUUUAAACAGAUAAUGAAAAAAUGGAAGAGAGGUUGUGGGGAGGAUCAGGUCCUAUUUUAUAUAUUAAAUCUGAGGUGCUAGUGAGGCAUGCAAGUAAAAAGACUGAGUUUGGAAUGAAAUACAGGAGUCUGGGAACGGUGUGGGCCGAAGGUAGAAAACUGGAAGUUAUCAGCUUAUAGUUGGUAUUGAAAGAUACAAAGAUAAAGACCUAAAAUACAGAAAUAAACCCCAAGGACUGAGGAAUCAGGUAUUUAGAGGUCUGCAAAGGAAAAACAACCAGCAAAGAGCAAUAAAUGUUAGUUCUCUUCCUUCUUAAGCCCCUCAAGGAAAGGACAGGAACCAUUACUUCUGGAUGCUACAUCAACUUUUUCGAUACUACUAUGCUAAUUUUAUAAUUAAGAAUUACCUCAAACUGAAAGGAUUUAAUGCAUUGACCCCUUAAAUACUAUAUUUUUCAACCGUGUGAAUUCUAGUAUGUCUUACGAUCAUGAUUAUUAUACCAUGCAUAUAAUUGACUGUACAAGCCUACAGUUUCUAGAUGAACCUCAUUCUUAUAACUGCUUGAAAAGAACAAGAUGAAGCUAAUGUUUUUAAAUGAUAAGUUCAUUUGUUUUAUUUCUAGUAAGAAAAAUUAAUUUUCUUCCUUGUUCAGAAGAUUGAUUUGUUUUGCUAAUUAUCUUGUAAAAAUGUGCUUUAUGUUAUGUGUGAAGUUCUCCAUAGAUAAUUUCAUUUUCAGUUAAACGCAGUAAGCAUUCACUGAACACCUACUCUAGGCCAAAUAUUUGGCAAGGUGCCAGCGGAAAAGGAAUGAAAUGACAGGCCCAGAACAUUUUUUAAACCAGUUUCCCUGGUUCUGUAUAGCAUAGCGUAGUGGAAUUCUGAAGUCUUAAAUUUGGAUGGACAUUUUGAAGGUGACAGCUCUCAAUCCUUUUUUAGUAGCCAUGGUAUUCAGAGAUUGUGAAACAGUCCAAUAAAACAACAAUGCCACA